AGACACUCCUAGCCUUGGGGCAGCUGCCGGGCGAGUCAGCGGAGUAGCGGCCAGCGGGCGAUGGAGACAGAGAGACACCCGACGAGAGGAGGCGGGGUGGGGGAGGCGGGGAGAGUGCGGGGGCGGAGGCUGGCAGGGGGCGCUGGAAGCUGGAGCGGUCCGUGCGCUCCCCGCGCCCGAGGGUGCAGGAGGCUCUGAAGCGGCUGCUGCACCGCGGGGCCCAGGCGGCGGCUGGGGGGCUGGGGGGCGCUGCCGCCGCCGCCGCCGGGGGCGUCGCUGGCCUCGGCCCCUUUGUUCUCGCGCGCUCCCCCUCGCCGCCCACUCCCCUGCUGUCGCGCGGCGGCGGCGGUGGCGGCGGCGGCUCCUCCCGCCCGAGGCAGUCGGGCUCGGCGCCGGGGGCGGGAGGGGGCGGGGGGAGCACGCCAGCCGCCGAGAGUGGGGGGCGAUGGCGAAGCUCCGGGUGGCUUACGAGUACACGGAAGCCGAGGACAAGAGCAUCCGGCUCGGCUUGUUUCUCAUCAUCUCCGGCGUCGUGUCGCUCUUCAUCUUCGGCUUCUGCUGGCUGAGUCCCGCGCUGCAGGAUCUGCAAGCCACGGAGGCCAAUUGCACGGUGCUGUCGGUGCAGCAGAUCGGCGAGGUGUUCGAGUGCACCUUCACCUGUGGCGCCGACUGCAGGGGCACCUCGCAGUACCCCUGCGUCCAGGUCUACGUGAACAACUCUGAGUCCAACUCUAGGGCGCUGCUGCACAGCGACGAGCACCAGCUCCUGACCAACCCCAAGUGCUCCUAUAUCCCUCCCUGUAAGAGAGAAAAUCAGAAGAAUUUGGAAAGUGUCAUGAAUUGGCAACAGUACUGGAAAGAUGAGAUUGGUUCCCAGCCAUUUACUUGCUAUUUUAAUCAACAUCAAAGGAUAAAGGCCAUGCUCUUCCAAUUCCAACUUAAACUUCUGCCAUUGAAUUAUGUGCCAGUCAAGGAAAACCAAAGACAAAACAACAAGAAAACAACAACAAAAUAGCAGACACGGUCCUUGCCUUCAUGGAGCCUAUAGUCUGUAGUCACAACAGUAGUAUAAUUACAAAGUAGGGUAGUGCUAUGAAGGGGAAGCUGAGGAUGCUGCUAUGAGAUAUUACGGCAUGAUGGGGAAUUUCAAAGACCUUUCUGUGUAAAUUAAAAUUAGGUCAAGACCAGAGGAUGUUCAAGAAUUAGCUAGGUAAAAAGCUAGGGGGAGAAUAUUUCAGAAUGAGAUACUACCAUGUGCCAAUGUUCUGCAGCAAAAAAGAGCUUGGUGGUUUUAGGUACUGGAAGGCCAGUGUGUCAGGAGAACUGUGAAUGAGUGGGAGAGUGGAGCAAGAACUAUACAGGGCUUAGAUUUCUCUUAAAAUGUAGUGAGCAGCCAGUCGUUGGUUUUAAGCAGAGUGGUAAUAUGGUCUGCUUUACAUAUUUUAACUUUUAUUCCAGCUGCAUCAGUCACCUCGAGUCAUUCUGUUUCCCAUACACCUUGAUGCCUUUGCUCCUGUCUCUUUCUCCUCACCUGGGGACACCUUCACCUUUUUUACUUCUGGGAAUUAGCACAGCACAGUAGUCCUAGAAUGAACUCUAGAACCAAACGCUUUCUAGUGGCGUGGUCUUAGAUAUGUUACUUAAAUCUAUCUGUGCCUCAGUUUCCUUUGCAGAAGUGGGAUAUAAUAUCAAGGAGAUGGCAUGUGCCUAACCCACAAUAAUUCCUACAAAAGUGUUUGCUAUUAUUGUUUUUAUUACUAUUAUUAAGAUUCACCUCAAAUGUUACUGUGUAACCUUCUCCCACCUUUUCAGGUAUAAUUCAUUACUUCCUCUUCUGCAGUCCCACACUGCCAUGGUUGCUUUUAUCACACUGUUAAGAGAGUUGAAUAUGUACUUUUUUGUUGUUAUAGAUUAUGAAUUCCUUAAGGGCAGCAGUCAUGUGACAUCAAGCAUCGGGAUUUACAUUUCUCCUCUAUCACUGAUUAAUUGUACGACCUUGGAUAAAUUGUGCAGCUUCUCCAUCUUGGUUUCCUCGCCUGUAAAAUGAGGAUAGCAUUACCCAUCUUAAGAGCUUCUGUUUUGGUUUUGUAAGAAACACAUUUGCACCAUAGCUAAUACUUAGUAAACACAUAUGCUUUUCUUCCCUGCCUCUGUAGAUUUCUAACAACUAAGUUAGAAACAAAGUUGGGCCUGGUUAUUUACUGAUUGGAGGCUGAGGUGUUGAAUAAAUAAAUAAUGAGGGUUUUAUGAAUGAGUAAAACAACAACACAAAAAAAAGGAAGAAAGAAGAAAUUCUGUUGUUAAAUAUGUUGUACUCCUGAUGCUAACAGAUAUAUCCUAAUUUCUAAGUUCACUCAAAGUGUGUUUAUCCUGUAGCAUAUGUUUUUAAAUCCAGUUUACCCUUAGCAUUUUAAAGAAAGAUAAACAUAAUGGCCUGAGCUCAAAUUGAGUAGUGGUUUCUUCAGAACACAGUUUUAAAGCCAUUAAAAUAGAAGAUGAAAAGCAACUGAUUAGAAAAAGACUGCUCACUUACUUAGGGUUUAGUUUUCUUAACUAUAAAAUUUGAUAGACUGAUGGAUGAAAUGAUCUCUAAAAUUCCUUCAAACUCUCAAAUUCUAUGGUUUUAUGAUUCCCUGGUUCUGAAGACUUGUACAAAAUUACAACAACUUAAGAUGCUAGAUAAAAUCCUAAUGGUGAAAGGGAGAGGCAAUUAGUAAAGAAAUAAAUGGUUAACAGUCUAGAGCCAUUUAAUGGAGAGGGAGACAGCCCUGCUACCUCAACGGUAAUUGAGUUUCAUAAUGAUGACACUGAGUCAUCAAAAAAGGUUAAAUUUGGUUCAACCUACUCUCCUUAAAAGGCAAAGAAAUGUGUAAUGCAUUUUUAGGAAGAUUUUUACCAAUAAUAUUUUAAUAUUUUAUUAGUUUUUAUUCAACUUAAAAUUUAAGCUUUAAUUAUUUGGAAAAUUCACUUUUGUAAAUGUCUAUUUCCUCUCCGUGAAGCAAGCCCAUUUCAGGGGCUACAGAGAUCUUCCUGCCGCCACAGAAUAGCUUAUCACUCUGGUAUCAUGGUUGUUACUCUUUUUGUAAUUUAGUGUCCUAAAUUUUACACAUAAAAAUGCUACCAUCUCAAGCUGGGAACAGUGGCAUAUACCUGUAGUCCCCACUACUUGGGAGGCUGAGAUGGGAGGAUCAUUUGAGUCCAGGAGUUUAAGGCUAGCCUGGGCAGCAUAGGGAGACCCUGUCUAAAAAAAGAAAAAAGAAAGUGGUAGAUGAACUGAAGAGGUUGAAAUAGAUAAUACUGUGCGUGUAUGUCAUGCUAAGGGGUUUAAAUUUGUCUUAAGGGCAGUGGAGGAGUGACAGUCACAUUUAAGUUUUAGAAAGAUGAGUCUAGUGGCAGCAUGGAGGGUAGAUUGAUAGAAGCCAAAGCUGGAGGAUCCAUGAACAAUUUGGAGACUGUUGUACCAGUCUAGACAAGGGAUGGUAGGAGCUUGGACAAAGGUAGAAUUAGUGGAGGAAGAAAAGGAGGAAUGGACAUAGGACUUGAAGGAAGUGGAAUCUGCAGAUUUAGAGAAGUACAUGAUGCUUGAUAGGGGUUGAGGUUAAGAACUGGAUGGAAUUGGAUCCAGUUCUGGCUUUCUGUCCUGGGUAACUGUUUUGGAGGCACCAUUAACUGGAAUGUUCUGGGAAAGCCUUUGCUUUUCUGAUGUGAGUGCUGCUGCCUCCUGCUUUCUGAUGCCACAACAGCAAAAGGCAUCAUGCAGCUUUGAGGUGAUAAACAGGAGAGUGGACAUCUACACAUUAGUAAGAGUGGAGCAAAAAGAGCCAGCUUCCUGGCACUCUUGUGGAAUAGCUGCCCCUGCCCUGGCCAUGCUACCUCUGGAUUUCUUGUUAUGUGUGACAGACAACACUUACAUGCUUAGAAAUAGGCAUCUGAAUAUGUUUAUAACCAAUAGAGUGAAAAAUGAUUGGUCAGUUGUAGUUUAUUUUCCGGACGUCUUUGCAUUCUAAAAACAGAUUGAGCUCUAAAAACAGAUGCAAGCUCAAAAAAAGAUUUAUUUUAAUAUAUUUAUAUGUUGAAUUUAAUUGUACCAUUGGCUUCUAAGUUUUUCUUUUGGCUUUUUUAUAGAGCAAAUUACUAAAGAAAAAACUUUGUUUUUACUAGCAGACCUCUUAGUAUACAAAUGGGGAAAAUGUGCAUAUAAAGAUGGGACCUAAGAUUUGGAACAAAUUCCAGAGGAAAAUUUUGUUGACAUUGGAAUGAAUUACUAAAUACUGUGUUUGAUAUUUGGUAAAAAUUACUUAUUUUUGUCUUCUACUCUGAGAAGUAUUUCUUACAGUCUUAUCAUUAGAGAAUAGACUGGUUCUAAGGCUAUUUUUUACAGGAACAUAUUGGCUUUUUCUUUAGACAUUAAACCCAAUGAUAUAUCCUGUAUCUUAAAAAACAAAACAGUAAAUCUGGAAUCUUACCGAAACCAAGUAUUUUCCAUAUACAUUUGUGUCUGUCUCCAUAUUAAGAGAGAUUACAUCAGAGUUGAAGGCUUUCUUUGGUCCCAAAAUCUGUACUUUUUAAAAAAAGCAGUGAUUGCUGUGGCUUCUCCAGUAUGCUGUGGAAUAUAUAUGGAAGUUAUUCCAGUGUUUUUUCUCAGUCUGACAUCCAAAUGGCUGUACAUUACUUAAAAUCUACAUUUGAGAGUCUGUUUUCUAAUGGUUAAUCAAAGUGUUUUCAUGCUUGCAAAUUCAUCUUCUAACAGCUUUUAUCAUCGUGGCAUUAAAGUUAAGAAUUUGAUGUUAUUAAAUCACUUUUCAUUUAAGAUAUUUUAUGCAGCCUUCAAACAAAGCCCUGAGGGAAUUUGGGAGGAAAAAUACAAGAACCGUAGGACAAGUAGGUCAUAGAGUGCAGCAUCAUCAGAUGGUGGAAUGCAGGGCAGGGCUGUGCGUCAGGAGACUCCACUCCAUUUCUAUCCAUGGCUCUCUUCGUGACUUAGUGAUUGACCUUGGGCUACUUAUCAAAGAGCUCUUGCCUCAGUUUCAUCUUAGAUAAAAUGGGGCUAGAAGUCACCGGAAACACAUGUCAAAUGUAUUGUGGAGUUCACAGACUCAUAGACUGUCAAAUCUGGGAGACACUUUUCAUUCAUUUGCUGCAACCCAAAAUGAAUCCCCACCACAUAAUUUUUUGAAGUGUUUUCUGUUCUCUACUUGAACGACUCUUGUGACAGUGGACAUCACCUCCUCCUGAAGAAACCCACUCCAUUUUUAAACGUUUUUAGUUGUCAAGAAAUUAAUCCUGGGAAAUACCUAAAAUAGGCAAAUUCAUAGAGACAGAAAGUAUAUUAAGUUUAUCAGGGACUGAGGGAAGUGGAAAGUGGGGAGCUAUUGCUCAAUGGCUAGAGAGUUUCUGUCUGGUGAGAUUUAAGUUUUGGGCUGGGUGCGGUGGCUCACACUUGUAAUCCCAGCACUUUGGGAGGCUGAGGCAGGCAGAUCAUGAGGUCAAGAGUUCGAGACCAGCCUGACCAACAUGGUGAAACCCCAUCUCUACCAAAAAUACAAAAAUUAGCCAGGCGUGGUGGUGCAUGCCUGUAAUCCCAGCUACUCAGGAGGCUGAGGCAGGAGAAUUGCUUGAACCCGGGAGGCAGAGAUUGCAGUGAGCUGAGAUCGCACCACUGCACUCUAGCCUGGGUGACAGAGCGAGACUCUGUCUCAAAAAAAAAGAUUUUGGAAAUAAAUUAUGUGAAUCUAAUUAAUGCCACUAAAUUGUGAGUCUAAUUAAUGCCACUCAGUUGUAUACUUUACCACAAUUUUUAAAGAUUCACUGUGGUUAGUUCUAUAAUCUCAGUGUGGAGGUAGACCAUAUUGUCCAAGUUUUACAGAAGAGACAACAGAGGCUUUAAGAUCACAUGGCUAGGGAGGAGCAGUGUCAGGAUCUGCACCUGAGUACUUGACCUUCAGACUGUGGGUGUCACCAAGUUCAUAUUGCCAUCACUGUUGGGAACAGAUUUGUUCUCAUCAUUUGGGAUGCUUUUCUUACUGUGCCCUGAGCUGGCCAGUGCAGAGGAAGGCAGAACAUUUCUACCACCCUUGAUAAAUCCAGAGACUGAAACUCAGUUAACGACAUGGCAUGAGCUUUUUUGGCAGCUACAGCACACUAUUGAUUCAUAUGGAGCUUAUACUUAAUUAAAUUUGCUCUCCCAACAUUUGAUUUAUACAUGCUGCUCUUUAUUAAAGCAGGUUCCCUCCAUUCUUAAACUGUUGAGAUUUGUGUAGCAUUUAAAUACGCAAGAAUUUAAAAUUUAUUCCUAUAUGUGACUACAUCUUGUUGCUUUUGACCGAUUGUUCCAGUCUCAUGAUUAUUUUGACUCUUGAUUAUGGUACCCAUCAUAUUUGUUAUAUCUUCCAUCAUAAUUCUAUCUUAAUUGUAAGUCAAAAUGGCUUUGAUUUUUCUCAUCCAAGUUAUCGAUAAAAAUGCUGAAAAGGACUAGGACAUAGACCUAUUUCACUGCUGAUCUUCCUUUGGCCUUUCAUAAUAGCCGAUACCUGUUUACCAUGCUGCCUCUGUACCAGAAACUAUUUAAAUGUUUUUUACAUAUUAACUCAUUGAAUCUGCACAACACCCCUACAAGGCAUUAUUAACACAAUCCUCAUUUUAUACAUGAGGGAACUGGAACACAGAGGUUAAGCAAUAUGACCAAAUCACAUAGCUGGCAAGUGACAGAGCCAGGAUUCAAACCUCUUAGUUCCAGAAGCCUCUUCUGUAAAACUUGGACAAUAUGGUCUACCUCCACACUGAGAUUACAGAACUAACCAUGGUGAAUCUUUAAAAAUUGUGGUAAAGUGCACAAUUUAGUGGCAUUAAUUAGACUCACAAUUUAGUGGCAUUAAUUAGAUUCACAGAGUCUGUUCUCUUAAGCAUUCUGCUCUGGUGCUGCUAACAUCAGCCAGGAUUCUAGUCCAUAUUGGGUUAGGAUAACAUAAGGGACUGUAUUAAAUCUAAUUAAUAAGAUUGCUAUUAUAACAUUUUUUAAAGUGCGUUGUUGGUGGCAAAAUAAUCUGAAAUGCCAGACCAAAGCAUUUGUGCUGUAUCUUCUACCAAGAAAUUCUUUCCCCAUUUUUUCACCAAACUCUAAUCUGUUCUUUCAUGUCUGCUGAAAAGAUACUUCCUUUUUAUUUUCCCAGGCAAACUUCAGUUCUCCUUCUUUAAUAUUACCUCUGCACUUUGUACAAAUGUCCAUUGCAUUUUGAAAUGGAUUUCAACAGUAAGCCAACAACAAACAUUUAUGAGCACCUAGAGCACAUGCCAAGCAUUAUUCUGGGUAAUGGGAAUAUAAACAUGGGAAAAUGGUGCUCCUGCCCUCGGAUUUACAGCUGACUAGUGAGAGCCAACACACAAAUAUGGCCCUGGUCCCUGCUACAUCAUAGUUGUUCUGCAAAUAUCACAUGGCUGAAUGGAAGAGAGCUGAGUACCAAGAAAGUCUUUUAAAAUGCCCAAAUAAACAUCUCUAAACUUUUUUGUGCUUUAGAUUAAGAUUAUUUUUGACCAUCAUGGCUGUUUCCUUAGUGAAACCAUUGGAUCCUCAGCCCUUCCUGGUGUGUGUCAAUGAGCUUAGGCUAAAUUAGGCUGUGGUAACAACCUGAAAAUCUCAGAAGCUUGUAACAACCAAUGUUUAUUUCCUGUCUAGGUCUGUCUUGGGUCGUGUGCAGCUCUGCUCCAUGUCAGUUUCACUAUGGGACCCCAGAUGAAGGAGGGGCACCUAUCUGGGACAUUAAUGCUAGUAUCAAGGUGAAAGAGCAGAAAACAGGUUUCUGUAGGAAUACCUGUGGCUAUACUUUUUAGUGAUUUUCAAAUUCUUUACCAUGUUUAUUCCACCAAUCUGACAGUUAUUUACAUGUGUUUUCUUGAAUUUUGAAUAUCACAUGCUACCAGGAUAAAGUUAAGCUGCUGGCACAUCUAAGAGAAACUUGAAGACUGAUAGGGUCUUUUUCAUUACUCAAGUUUUAAAAUUCUAUUGUUGAACUGUAAGUCACCACUUUAAUUGUUAUGCAUAUUUCUGUAUAGUAUUUUUGUUCUCCAAACAUAUUUGUAAUCCUUCAUUUAGGAAAAGAGCCUCAAAAUUAAUUUAGCUAAUUUUACUUUGCAAAGGCAUUUCAAGAUGUUUAAUGCAUUUUAACUGAGAGAUAUUGCUUGACAGACUACAACAAAAUUGAAUGUAAAAAUUGAAUGUAUAGUAAAGUAUUCUUUACUAUAUAAUUUAGGGGUUAGGAUGAAUGAUUCAUUGCUAGCCUUGAUAGAAAUGCUAGCCUAUUUCUGUCUUCCUACAAGCAAUAGCAAAAUAUAUAUAAGCUGCUAAUUAUUUAAUUUAAAAAAACCGGUGUGUAAUACACUUUAAUGAAAUAGGCUGUUAACAAUUGGGAAUCUUCUAGAAUGAUGAUAUUAUAACAGAAGGUAGCGCUUUCUUCAGAAAGACAUGCAGCUGACUUUCCCUUCACCCAGGAUAUAUUUUUCAAAUCCUUUCUCCAGAGCUGCCAAAAUAAUGGUACAAUACUGAUGCUGGAGCUAUAGAAAAGAAAAUAAAUUGUGGUGAUGGGUAGAUUUUUCUUCACUGAGGAUCUAAUUACAGGGAAUUGGACUUAACCUAAUCAGACUUUAACGACAAUUUCCUAAGAGUAAAUUAGGGAACAAAUUACUGUGAGAUGAGUUGCAGAAUCUUUUUCAGAGGUUUGGAGAAAGACAGAAUGUCUGUUCACCUGUUUGGCCCCAUUUAGUAUUGGCUUAACCAGGCGCUGGCAGCAGUUCCUAGCAUGCUGGGUCUGAAAUUGUGACAUGUAUAGGAGCAGCAGCAUUGGAGGCUCCUCAAGGAGGACAAAGCACCUAAACAGGGAUGGGGCAGGUGAGUUGAAGGAACAGGAACUGCUUGUGACAGUUGUUAUGCACACAUUGGGGUUGGCUGGGCUAGAUAGAGAUCGAUUAAAAGAUGAAGCAGGAAGAAGAACAGUAAUGACAGAAUGAGUAGUAAAUAUGAUCAUUCAUUCUUGGAAAUUAUCUGAAAAUAGUUGGCACAGUCUGUAAAAACACAAGCAAAUACACAUGCCUGUUUAUGCAAAUACAUCCAUGAUAUUUGCAAUUUCAAACAAAUAUAUGUGGCCUUUGGAAAAAACCUCCAUGAAAUCUAAGAUCUUGUUCCCUGCCCGCUACCUUAAUUUGCUUAACUGACACUCUAUGGCACUGGAUUUUCACUUUCUUCUUUGAAGUCUUUUCUUAUUCCACUAACAUUUACUGAGCUCUCACUUUGAGCUUAGCAGGGUGUGAUGCUCUUCUAGGAGCGGGAAUACUGGGAAAAAAAUCCAGGUUAUUGGGAGUUGAACAAACUCACUGAGACCACCGACCAUUCUUUAUGGGGGCAUUUGUGGUUGAGCCAUGGGAGACUCAGCUAGCCCGUGUUGCUAUGCCCCACUUCAAUUGUCCUAUCUAAGAAGCCAUCUUGAUUUUAUAUCAAAAUUCAUGGGGAAAAUGUGCCUUGACUUCCUUUUAAAUGCCUUAUUUUGUCUGUGCACAUCAUACCCAGGACUGUUGAGAUGGUAAGAAGAUACAUUGGCAUUUGGGGGGAUUCCUUACCCACCUCAUUUCCUUGAGAACCAAAUUCUAAAGCUCUUGCCAGCCUUACAGACACCCAAUGGAAUCCCUGCUCAUAUGCAUAUUUUGGGUGCAUCAGUAUGUUUGUCAUUUUCUCCCUGGAAACGGUUUCUCACACCCACGUUGCAAGUGUGUGAUCUGUGAUUAUAUCUCUUUUCUGUGUCCUCUUUGCCUGGAGCGAGGGCUGAGAACAUGAUUCAGCUUAGGGAAAUGAUACAAAAUGUGGUUGUUAAAGUGAUCUUUCAAAAAGCAGCUUUUUAUAUGUGUGCAGUCACUAUGCUUGGUGUAGCCUAUGACUUCAUUCACCUGAAGCAAUGAAGCAGAUUCCAGGAUUUUAGAAUUAUGGUCUUGGACAAACCUAGAAGACACCUGCUUUUAGGCCCUUGGAUAUAAUCUUAUUUCAUUUAAAAGAUUUUGAAGAUUUUGAGACAAAGGCGCGUGCUAACUUUGCUCCGUGAUUAAUCCUUCCAGAGUUUGUUGCCAUCUUGAUUUUAUAUCAAAAAUCAUGAGGAAAAUGUUUCUUGACCUCCUUUUAAAUGCCAUAUUUCAUCUGUGCACAUUGUACCCAGGAUUGUUGAGAUGGUAAGAAGAUACAUUGACAUUUGGGGGGAUUCCUUACCCACCUCAUUUCCUUGAGAACCAAAUUCUAAAGCUCUUGCCAGCCUUAUAGAUACCCAAUGGAAUCCCUGCUCAUAUGCAUACUUUGGGUUCAUCGGUGAUUUUUGCUCACUGUGACUAAUCCUUCCAGUGUUUGUAGCCUUUCUUAUAAGGAGAACUUCUAUUUCAGCUUUGUUAAUUUGGCUUCACAAAGUAAAAUAAGGGGCCCCAUUGUUUUGUCUUAAUCAGUGAAGGGAAUAUGGGAUGUCCUGAUAUAAUUAGUCCUUUGAUUUUUAGUCCUAUCCAGCCCGGGCUUGCUUGAGAAGUCCCUUGUGUAGCCCUAUAUUAUCAGACAUGCUAUAUCACAGCAAGCACCUUUUGAUGUUUAAGAAUUAAUUCCUUUAAGGAAUUCUAAAAAAGAAAGAUAUUUUCAGCAUUAACAUCCUAAAUCAACAUUUCCAUUUUCUGAGGAUGUUUCUUUAGCACUAGGCAUCGCUGAGAUAGAAAAUGAGUUCUGAGAGACUUUCUUUGGAAACAAAAUGGCUCACCCUUAAAUUUCCCCGUUUCUGGAUGAAAUCUGAUUUAAUAAUACAGUAUUGCUCUUCAAAUAUGAGAGAAAUCAUUGUAAGGAAGAAUGUGGGUUUUAAAGAAUAGAAUGGGUUGGAUAAAUGUUUUUAUAAAAUAGAAGUGAAAGGAUCAGAAAUCAGCAGUAUCAAAACAACAAGAAGAACUGAUUAAACCAUGCACUUGUUACCUCUGAAUUUCUCUUUGCAGAAAUUCUACUUCAAUUUUAAAAUUCAGAAUUAAAAAAAAAUAUUCAAAGGAUAGUUAAUGAACAAAAACUUUAGGAAAGUCAAACAUGGUGUGGCAUAGGAUUGGGGCUAAAGUGAAUAUGCAGUUUAGAAUUGCUAGUGACAUUGUAUCAUAAAAGAACUGAGUAAAGAAGAACCAAGAAUCUUUGGGCACAUUUGAUAAAAAAUAAAGUUGAAAAGGAAAUAUCAAAGAUGUAUUACAAAGACAAAAAGGAUAUUCUAUAAAAAGUAAGGAGGCACUUAGGGAGGAUGGAUAUUAAAAUUGCAAAGUGUUAUUAAUGCUGUGGUUAGGAACAGCAGAUAGUGGUGGAAAUAGUGGAGAUCUACCUAGGCAAAGGCACAAUGUAGGAAAAGGAUGAAGGAAAGAGAAGUAUUUCAUAACGUGUGCUAAUCUUUGGGCAGGUGUGUCUUGUAUGUAAAUGCCUGUCAUAAAAGGCAAACACUGAAAAAAGAAUGAAAAAAGUAAAUCUUAUAACUCAGAUUGUAGAUCUGAGUUAUAAAAUAGAAUUAAUAGAAAACAGUUUAUUCCCUAGGUUAUUUUUAAAUACUUCUGUUGAUGAUUUAAUUCUGAAUGACUAACUGGGAAAGGGGAUAGAAAACUUGUGCUAGUAAGGAACUGAUUACAGUAUAGGAGAGCGGUUUAUGGUACUGUGGCUGUCUGAAUAGUGGCCCCCAAAGAUGUCCACACCAUAAUCCCGAUGGAUUUAUGUUAUUUUACUUUGCUACCAUGUUACCUUGUAUGAUAAAAGGAACUUUGCAGAUGUGAUUAAGGAUUUUGAGAUGGGGAAAUUAUACUGGAUUGCCUGAGUGUGCCCCAAAUGCAAUCAUGGGAUACUUAUAAGGGGGAGAUGAGAUCAGAGAGAGUAGUAGGGGAUGUGAUCAGGGAAAGGAGAUUAGAGUGAUGCCAGGGAGGGGGCCAUGAGCCAAAGAAUGCAGGAAAGGAUGCUGGGAAAGGCAAGGAAACAGAUUCUCUCCUAGAACCUCCAGAAGGAACACAGCCCUGCUGACACCUUCAUUUUAGUCCAGUGAAACAGAUUGCAAACCUCUGACCUCCAGAACUGUAAGAAACUACAUCUGUGUUGCUUUAAGCUACUAGAGCAGCAAUAGGAAAUAGAUACAGGCAGUAAUUUGCAGAUAGUUCUAAGUGUAAUUGACUUUUACAAUGAAUAUGAGCUUUUCUUCAACUUUGAGCUUUGAAAAUACUACAGAUUGCCAGGCGCAGUGGCUCACACCUGUAAUCCCAGCACUUUGGGAGGCCGAGGCGGGCGGAUCAUGAGGUCAAGAGAUCGAGACCAUCCUGGCUAACACGGUGAAACCCCGUCUCUACUAAAAAUACAAAAAAUUAGCCGGGCGUGGUGGCAGGCACCUGUAGUCCCAGCGGGAGGCUGAGGCAGGAGAAUGGUGUGAACCUGGGAGGGGAGCUUCCAGUGAGCUGAGAUAGCGCCACUGCACUCCAGCCUGGGCGACGUAGCGAGACUCCGUCUCAAAAAAAAAAAAAAAAAUACUACAAAUUUUAAAAGGUUCUGGUUCUGUAUCAUACUCUUGGGGUUGUCAAAUUCAUUUCUUCAAGGUUGGAAAAGUUGGACUUGGACUAGAUUUGAGGUCACCUAUGCUGUGUAGGGUUUUGUAGAAAACUGCUUCCCAGCUGAGUAUGGUCGCUCAUAUCUGUAAUCCCAGUGCUUUGGGAGCCCAAAGUUGGAGGAUUGCUUGAGUCCAGAGUUCGAGACUGGCCUGGGUAACAUAAUGAGAUCCUGUCUCUACAAAAAAUUGUAAAAAUUAGCUGAGCGUGAUGGUGGGCACCUGUAGUCCCAGCUACUAGGGAGGCUGAGGUGAGAGGAUUGCUUGAGCCCAGGAGGUUAAGCACUCCAGCCUGGGCGACAGAGUGAGACCUUGUCUCAAAAAAGAAAAAAAAAAAAAAAAAAAAAAACUUUUCCCAUACAUACCCUCAUUUGAUCUUCUUAAUGAGGGUUUUAUUUCCCAUUUUACAAAUGAGGAAACUCCAAGGGUUUUUAUUUAUUUAUUUAUUUAUUUUUGAGACAGAGUCUCGCUCUGUCGCCCAGGCUGGAGUGCAGUGGCGCAAUCUUGGCUCACUGCAAGCUCCACCUCCCAAGUUCACGCCAUUCUCCUGCCUCAGCCUCCCGAGUAGCUGGGACUACAGGUGGCCGCCACCACACCCAUCUAAUUUUUUGUAUUUUUAGUAGAGACGAGGUUUCACUAUGUUAGCCAGGAUGGUCUUGACCCCCUGACCUCUUGAUCCGCCCGCCUUGGCCUCCCAAAGUGCUGGGAUUACAGGCGUGAGCCAGCAUGCCUGGCCUUUUUUUUUUUUUUUUUAACGAAGUUAUUUUUCUAGAGCAUUCAUAGUUUGUUUUUAUACAGUUAAGGUUCUCAUCCAUCUGGAUUUUUUGGUAAGUGUGGGGAGAAUAAAAUGAGGAGCCGCUGUUUUUUUCUCCAAAUGGCAUGUAUUGUCCCAACACAAUUUAUUGAAUCAAUAAUUCAUCUCUCCCAUACGAAUUUAAACUAUUGAACUUUCACAUCAAAUUUGGAACUACAAAGUAGGUUAACAAGGUGAGAACUAUUAUAAGAAUAAUCUGUCUCAAAUGAAGAAUGUAAAUGUCUUCUUGUCUCCAGUUUAUUUCUGCUUAAACCUUAAGUUUAAAUGUUUGGACAGAAAAACACUUAUAGUCCUCUAUGAAAUAAAUAACUUGGUAACUCAGAGAAACCACAGACCAAAUUACUCUGAAGAACAGCAAUUCUUAAAGGAAACCUCUCAGGAAUUUCUGGAACAAGGCUGUCAGCUAGUUUUCAAAAUCCUGCACUUCUGAUGAAAUCAAUGAAUUGAAAGUCCUCCUCUCUGGUGUGGAGAUAACGUUGAACUGAUCCAGGUUCCUGAGCAGCUCAAGGAGGUCGAUGGAAGAGGAAAAGGAUUUAAUGUAAAUUUAAUGCAGUUUCUUAGAUCUGAUCUUAGAGAAUAUCUAACUAGGUUGAAAAUUCUCUUUCUGUUGUAUUUUCAAUGGAAGAGCAACAAAGGAUUUCUAAUUAAUAAAGCCUUUUUGUGCCAA